AGUCAGCCCUGCUGCCAGCCAGUGCCGGGUGCUGGGGACUCAGGGAGGCCCGCCGGGACCACUGCGGGACAGUGAGCCGAGCAGAAGCUGGAACGCAGGAGAGGAAGGAGAGGGGGCGGUCAGGGCUCUCAGGAGCCGGGUCCUGGGCAAGGCGCAGCCGUUUUCAAAUUUUCAGGAAAGCGGUCGGCUCACACUCGAGCAGUAAAAAGAUGCCUCUGGGGAGGAGGCCCGUGCAGCUCUCCGGGCAAUGGUGGUGGCUCGGCCUAGAGAGGCGGUAGUGGAACGCAGACCCUGGUGGGGGAAUGACAUCAAGGGAGGAGACGGGCGGGACCCCAGAUUUCUGCCUGUGGGCGAUGGAAGUGAGGUUCACUGGCCAGCGGAGCCGGACACAGAACGCGCAAAACGCCGUGUAGGCCUGGAGGAGCCGAAGAGCAGGCGGACCCCCUCCGCGGGGGAACAGUUUCCGCCGGGAGCACAAAGCAACGGACCGGAAGUGGGGGGCGGAAGUGCAGUGGGCUCAGCGCCGACUGCGCGCCUCUGCCCGCGAAAACUCUGAGCUGGCUGACAGCUGGGGACGGGUGGCGGCCCUCGACUGGAGUCGGUUGAGUUCCUGAGGGACCCCGGUUCUGGAAGGUUCGCCGCGGAGACAAAAGGUGAAUGGCAUCCUGGAGAGCCCUACGGGUACAGGGAAGACGCUGUGCCUGCUGUGCACCACGCUGGCCUGGCGAGAACACCUCCGAGACGGCAUCUCUGCCCGCAAGAUUGCCGAGAGGGCGCAAGGAGAGCUUUUCCCGGAUCGGGCCUUGUCAUCCUGGGGCAACGCUGCUGCUGCUGCUGGAGACCCCAUAGCUUGCUACACGGACAUCCCAAAGAUUAUUUACGCCUCCAGGACCCACUCGCAACUCACACAGGUCAUCAACGAGCUUCGGAACACCUCCUACCGGCCUAAGGUGUGUGUGCUGGGCUCCCGGGAGCAGCUGUGCAUCCAUCCUGAGGUGAAGAAACAAGAGAGUAACCAUCUACAGAUCCACUUGUGCCGUAAGAAGGUGGCAAGUCGCUCCUGUCAUUUCUACAACAACGUAGAAGAAAAAAGCCUGGAGCAGGAGCUGGCCAGCCCCAUCCUGGACAUUGAGGACUUGGUCAAGAGCGGAAGCAAGCACAGGGUGUGCCCUUACUACCUGUCCCGGAACCUGAAGCAGCAAGCCGACAUCAUAUUCAUGCCGUACAAUUACUUGUUGGAUGCCAAGAGCCGCAGAGCACACAACAUUGACCUGAAGGGGACAGUCGUGAUCUUUGACGAAGCUCACAACGUGGAGAAGAUGUGUGAAGAAUCGGCAUCCUUUGACCUGACUCCCCAUGACCUGGCUUCAGGACUGGACGUCAUAGACCAGGUGCUGGAGGAGCAGACCAAGGCAGCGCAGCAGGGUGAGCCCCACCCGGAGUUCAGCGCGGACUCCCCCAGCCCAGGGCUGAACAUGGAGCUGGAAGACAUUGCAAAGCUGAAGAUGAUCCUGCUGCGCCUGGAGGGGGCCAUCGAUGCUGUUGAGCUGCCUGGAGACGACAGCGGUGUCACCAAGCCAGGGAGCUACAUCUUUGAGCUGUUUGCUGAAGCCCAGAUCACGUUUCAGACCAAGGGCUGCAUCCUGGACUCGCUGGACCAGAUCAUCCAGCACCUGGCAGGACGUGCUGGAGUGUUCACCAACACGGCCGGACUGCAGAAGCUGGCGGACAUUAUCCAGAUUGUGUUCAGUGUGGACCCCUCCGAGGGCAGCCCUGGUUCCCCAGCAGGGCUGGGGGCCUUACAGUCCUAUAAGGUGCACAUCCAUCCUGAUGCUGGUCACCGGAGGACGGCUCAGCGGUCUGAUGCCUGGAGCACCACUGCAGCCAGAAAGCGAGGGAAGGUGCUGAGCUACUGGUGCUUCAGUCCCGGCCACAGCAUGCACGAGCUGGUCCGCCAGGGCGUCCGCUCCCUCAUCCUUACCAGCGGCACGCUGGCCCCGGUGUCCUCCUUUGCUCUGGAGAUGCAGAUCCCUUUCCCAGUCUGCCUGGAGAACCCACACAUCAUCGACAAGCACCAGAUCUGGGUGGGGGUCGUCCCCAGAGGCCCCGAUGGAGCCCAGUUGAGCUCCGCGUUUGACAGACGGUUUUCCGAGGAGUGCUUAUCCUCCCUGGGGAAGGCUCUGGGCAACAUCGCCCGCGUGGUGCCCUAUGGGCUCCUGAUCUUCUUCCCUUCCUAUCCUGUCAUGGAGAAGAGCCUGGAGUUCUGGCGGGCCCGCGACUUGGCCAGGAAGAUGGAGGCGCUGAAGCCGCUGUUUGUGGAGCCCAGGAGCAAAGGCAGCUUCUCCGAGACCAUCAGUGCUUACUAUGCAAGGGUUGCCGCCCCUGGGUCCACCGGCGCCACCUUCCUGGCGGUCUGCCGGGGCAAGGCCAGCGAGGGGCUGGACUUCUCAGACACGAAUGGCCGUGGUGUGAUUGUCACGGGCCUCCCGUACCCCCCACGCAUGGACCCCCGGGUUGUCCUCAAGAUGCAGUUCCUGGAUGAGAUGAAGGGCCAGGGUGGGGCUGGGGGCCAGUUCCUCUCUGGGCAGGAGUGGUACCGGCAGCAGGCGUCCAGGGCUGUGAACCAGGCCAUCGGGCGAGUGAUCCGGCACCGCCAGGACUACGGAGCUGUCUUCCUCUGUGACCACAGGUUCGCCUUUGCCGACGCAAGAGCCCAACUGCCCUCCUGGGUGCGUCCCCACGUCAGGGUGUAUGACAACUUUGGCCAUGUCAUCCGAGACGUGGCCCAGUUCUUCCGUGUUGCCGAGCGAACUAUGCCAGCGCCGGCCCCCCGGGCUACAGCACCCAGUGUGCGUGGAGAAGAUGCUGUCAGCGAGGCCAAGUCGCCUGGCCCCUUCUUCUCCACCAGGAAAGCUAAGAGUCUGGACCUGCAUGUCCCCAGCCUGAAGCAGAGGUCCUCAGGGUCACCAGCUGCCGGGGACCCCGAGAGUAGCCUGUGUGUGGAGUAUGAGCAGGAGCCAGUUCCUGCCCGGCAGAGGCCCAGGGGGCUGCUGGCCGCCCUGGAGCACAGCGAACAGCGGGCGGGGAGCCCUGGCGAGGAGCAGGCCCACAGCUGCUCCACCCUGUCCCUCCUGUCUGAGAAGAGGCCGGCAGAAGAACCGCGAGGAGGGAGGAAGAAGAUCCGGCUGGUCAGCCACCCGGAGGAGCCCGUGGCUGGUGCACAGACGGACAGGGCCAAGCUCUUCAUGGUGGCCGUGAAGCAGGAGUUGAGCCAAGCCAACUUUGCCACCUUCACCCAGGCCCUGCAGGACUACAAGGGUUCCGAUGACUUCGCCGCCCUGGCCGCCUGUCUCGGCCCCCUCUUUGCUGAGGACCCCAAGAAGCACAACCUGCUCCAAGGCUUCUACCAGUUUGUGCGGCCCCACCAUAAGCAGCAGUUUGAGGAGGUCUGUAUCCAGCUGACAGGACGAGGCUGUGGCUAUCGGCCUGAGCACAGCAUUCCCCGAAGGCAGCGGGCACAGCCGGUCCUGGACCCCACUGGAAGAACGGCGCCGGAUCCCAAGCUGACCGUGUCCACGGCUGCAGCCCAGCAGCUGGACCCCCAAGAGCACCUGAACCAGGGCAGGCCCCACCUGUCGCCCAGGCCACCCCCAACAGGAGACCCUGGCAGCCAACCACAGUGGGGGUCUGGAGUGCCCAGAGCAGGGAAGCAGGGCCAGCACGCCGUGAGCGCCUACCUGGCUGAUGCCCGCAGGGCCCUGGGGUCCGCGGGCUGUAGCCAACUCUUGGCAGCGCUGACAGCCUAUAAGCAAGACGACGACCUCGACAAGGUGCUGGCUGUGUUGGCCGCCCUGACCACUGCAAAGCCAGAGGACUUCCCCCUGCUGCACAGGUUCAGCAUGUUUGUGCGUCCACACCACAAGCAGCGCUUCUCACAGACGUGCACAGACCUGACCGGCCGGCCCUACCCGGGCAUGGAGCCACCGGGACCCCAGGAGGAGAGGCUUGCCGUGCCUCCUGUGCUUACCCACAGGGCUCCCCAACCAGGCCCCUCACGGUCCGAGAAGACCGGGAAGACCCAGAGCAAGAUCUCGUCCUUCCUUAGACAGAGGCCAGCAGGGACUGUGGGGGCGGGCGGUGAGGAUGCAGGUCCCAGCCAGUCCUCAGGACCUCCCCACGGGCCUGCAGCAUCUGAGUGGGGCCUCUAGGAUGUGCCCAGCCUGCCACACCGCCUCCAGGAAGCAGAGCGUCAUGCAGGUCUUCUGGCCAGAGCCCCAGUGAGUGCCCACGGAGGCCCCCAGCACACCCAACGUGGCUUGAUCACCUGCCUGUCCAGCUCUGGUGGGCCAAGAACCCACCCAACAGAAUAGGCCAGCCCAUGCCAGCCGGCUUGGCCCGCUGCAGGCCUCAGGCAGGCGGGGCCCAUGGUUGGUCCCUGCGGUGGGACCGGAUCUGGGCCUGCCUCUGAGAAGCCCUGAGCUACCUUGGGGUCUGGGGUGGGUUUCUGGGAAAGUGCUUCCCCAGAACUUCCCUGGCUCCUGGCCUGUGAGUGGUGCCACAGGGGCACCCCAGCUGAGCCCCUCACCGGGAAGGAGGAGACCCCCGUGGGCACGUGUCCACUUUUAAUCAGGGGACAGGGCUCUCUAAUAAAGCUGCUGGCAGUGCCCAGGACGGUG